ACACACCCUCGGGGAGGACCAGCAUCCAAGCAGGUGGAAGGGCUCUGAGGGAGACUGGAAUUUUCUGGCCUGGAGAAGGACCCGCCCGCCCGCCCCUAUGACCAACAUGAGCUGGAGCUUCCUGACGCGGCUGCUGGAGGAGAUCCACAACCACUCCACCUUCGUGGGCAAGGUGUGGCUCACGGUGCUGGUGGUCUUCCGCAUCGUGCUGACGGCUGUGGGCGGCGAGGCCAUCUACUCGGACGAGCAGGCCAAGUUCACUUGCAACACGCGGCAGCCAGGCUGCGACAACGUCUGCUAUGACGCCUUCGCGCCCCUGUCGCACGUGCGCUUCUGGGUCUUCCAGAUUGUGGUCAUCUCCACGCCCUCGGUCAUGUACCUGGGCUACGCCGUGCACCGCCUGGCCCGUGCGUCUGAGCAGGAGCGGCGCCGCGCCCUCCGCCGCCGCCCGGGGCCACGCCGCGCGCCCCGAGCGCACCUGCCGCCCCCGCACGCCGGCUGGCCUGAGCCCGCCGACCUGGGCGAGGAGGAGCCCAUGCUGGGCCUGGGCGAGGAGGAGGAGGAGGAGGAGACGGGGGCAGCCGAGGGCGCCGGCGAGGAAGCGGAGGAGGCAGGCGCGGAGGAGGCGUGCACUAAGGCGGUCGGCGCUGACGGCAAGGCGGCAGGGACCCCGGGCCCGACCGGGCAACACGAUGGGCGGAGGCGCAUCCAGCGGGAGGGCCUGAUGCGCGUGUACGUGGCCCAGCUGGUGGCCAGGGCAGCUUUCGAGGUGGCCUUCCUGGUGGGCCAGUACCUGCUGUACGGCUUCGAGGUGCGACCGUUCUUUCCCUGCAGCCGCCAGCCCUGCCCGCACGUGGUGGACUGCUUCGUGUCGCGCCCUACUGAAAAGACGGUCUUCCUGCUGGUUAUGUACGUGGUCAGCUGCCUGUGCCUGCUGCUCAACCUCUGUGAGAUGGCCCACCUGGGCUUGGGCAGCGCGCAGGACGCGGUGCGCGGCCGCCGCGGCCCCCCGGCCUCCGCCCCCGCCCCCGCGCCGCGGCCCCCGCCCUGCGCCUUCCCUGCGGCGGCCGCUGGCUUGGCCUGCCCGCCCGACUACAGCCUGGUGGUGCGGGCGGCCGAGCGCGCUCGGGCGCAUGACCAGAACCUGGCAAACCUGGCCCUGCAGGCGCUGCGCGACGGGGCAGCGGCUGGGGACCGCGACCGGGACAGUUCGCCGUGCGUCGGCCUCCCUGCGGCCUCCCGGGGGCCCCCCAGAGCAGGCGCCCCCGCGUCCCGGACGGGCAGUGCUACCUCUGCGGGCACUGUCGGGGAGCAGGGCCGGCCCGGCACCCACGAGCGGCCAGGAGCCAAGCCCAGGGCUGGCUCCGAGAAGGGCAGUGCCAGCAGCAGGGACGGGAAGACCACCGUGUGGAUCUGAGGGCGCUGGCUUGCGAGCUGGGCCAGGGAGGAGGAGGGUUGGGGGGCUCCGGUGGAAACCUGCGACCCCUUCUCCUCAGCCUUCUCCUUAGCCGGUGGCCUCAGGCAGACUCUGCCCAGAGGGGCAGCCAGGCUGCUCAGGGAAGGGGCUGAAAGCGGCAGAGGAGUGCCCUGGCUUGGUCACCACUGGGGCCAAGGUGGGGUGGAGAGAGGCCUAGGAGCCAGAAAGGGCCCUCUGCUGUGGUCUGAACCCCAGGGGGAGUGGGGCAUUGACUCCACCCCUGUCCUGAGCUGGAAUAGGUCCUCUGGGAUGCCAGCUCUCCCCUUUGUGCUUCCCUGCAGCAACCCAUGGAGGGCCCAGGGUGCCUGGUAUGGGCAUCAGUUGGUGGGGGUGCGGGGGUGCGUGUCCCCAUUCCCUGCAACAGCAAAUGGGGCUCCUUCUUCAGCCCUCCCCUUCCCAGCCCCAAACUGAGACAGACUGGGAGCUGGGAGCCUGGGGUGGACAGGACCAUACCCUCUUUGAGCUUCUGCGAUGCCGGCCUUCCGUUCCUCUGGGAGGCUUGAAGUUCUGCAAAGAUGUUGAUAUGCCUUGCAGCUUGGACCCAAUGGGUGGUGGUCAGGGCCUGGGGGCUUGGCCAUGCUGGGGGAAUGGGGCUCUGGGUUCCUGCCUGUGGCCUGUCUGUCCUCCUCCCUAAUUCAGACCCAGCCUCAAGAGGAAAGGGAGUAAAAUAAAACUAACUUGUUUAUAA